AGCCGCAGGAAUAUGCUGGAAGGCGGCGGGCGGGCGCCCGCGAGGUGCUGAAAGGACAGUUCCCGCCGCCGAACUUAGCCCGCGGGUGGGGCGGCCCGGGAGCCAGCGGGGCACGUGAGCGAUGGAGACCAUCUGGAUCUACCAGUUCCGCCUCAUCGUGAUCGGGGACUCCACCGUGGGCAAGUCCUGCCUCCUGCACCGCUUCACCCAGGGCCGCUUCCCCGGGCUGCGCUCCCCCGCCUGCGACCCCACCGUCGGCGUGGACUUCUUCUCCCGCCUGCUGGAGAUCGAGCCGGGCAAGAGGAUCAAGCUACAGCUCUGGGACACGGCGGGACAGGAGCGGUUCAGAUCAAUAACCCGAUCUUAUUACCGCAACUCAGUUGGUGGAUUUUUAGUAUUUGACAUUACUAACCGACGAUCUUUUGAACAUGUGAAAGAUUGGCUAGAAGAAGCAAAAAUGUAUGUACAGCCAUUUCGGAUUGUAUUUCUGCUAGUGGGACAUAAAUGUGAUUUAGCUUCACAACGUCAAGUUACAAGGGAAGAAGCUGAAAAACUGUCAGCAGACUGUGGAAUGAAGUAUAUAGAAACCUCAGCAAAGGAUGCUACAAAUGUUGAAGAAUCCUUCACAAUCUUGACGAGAGACAUAUAUGAACUUAUUAAAAAGGGAGAAAUUUGUAUUCAGGAUGGCUGGGAAGGGGUUAAAAGUGGUUUUGUUCCAAAUACUGUGCAUUCUUCUGAGGAAGCAGUAAAGCCCAGGAAAGAAUGCUUCUGCUGACUUCAAACAUGCUGAAGAACUAACAGGAACAGAUUGGGUGUCAGUUCAGGAUAAAUACCAACAUUAACAGCAGAAUGAUGCAAUGAAAGAAUUUAAAAAGGUUACAAACCCACACCAAUACUAUUUUAUAAGGUAUUUGAUUCAGAGCAUGAUGCUUACUUGUUACACUACUAGAUUGGGUAUUUUGCUAAAUUACCAAGCAAAGCAGACAAUCUUUUUCUUGAAAUUACCUCCAUUCUUACUUUGUUAGCAUACGCUGACCUUAGUGUCCAGAUAUGUCACUAUUACUCAUUUUUCUUGACAGUUCAAAUGGAUUUUUGUGCAUAUAUAGUCAAUUGAAAAGAUUUUAUCAGGAAUUACAUUCUCUUGAGUUAAUUAAUAUUGAAUAGCAAAAUGCAUUUAAAUAUGCACUGUUCACCUGCAGAGUAAACAAUCUCAGAAGUAUCGACUAGGACGUAAAUAGCAGUUCCUUAUAUAAAGUACCAGGUUUUUUCCCCAUUCUCUGGAAAUGUUUGUCCUCCCUUAAUUUUGCCUCAACACAAGAAAAUAAGUUUUAUGUCCAUUUUUGUUCCCUAAUUUAUUGCUUCUAAAAAUGCAUUAUGUUUUACAAAGAUAUCUAAGGAUCCAAGCAAACUACUUUAAGCAAAUAUUUGUAAAAUUAAAAACGGAGGACCGCUCACCAAAUGUUUGAAAUGUUGCUUUUUUUUUUUGAGACAGGGUCUUGUUUUGUCACCCAGGCUGGAGUGCAGUGGGGCAAUCUUGGCUCCCUGCAACCUCUGCUUCCUGGGUUCAGGUGAUUGUCAGUACCUUACCUCAGCCUCCUGAGUAGCUGGAACUGCAGAUGUGCGCCACCAUGCCCGGCUAAUUUUUGUAUUAUAAGUAGACACAGGGUUUCAUAAUGUUCCCCAGGCUGGUCUCCAACUCCUCGCCUCAAGCAAUUCGCCCCCCUCGGCCUCCAAAGUGCUGGAAUUAUAGGCAUGAGCUGCCGUGCCUGGACUAUCAGCAGCACAUGUUUUGCUGUUACGGUGUACUGUUCGUAUUUAGACAAGAAGAACAAAAUUUAUUUAUGUAUUGACAUUUUCAAAGAAAGUAAAUGCAAUUUACUUUGAA